AUUCUAGUGCAGCCCUGGUUACGCCUCCUCUGGCUCAGUCACACAGCGACGUAGAGGUGACUGGAGGUAUAUACUUGUCCUCACCUGGAUCAUGCUGAUGUGGCCCCAACCCCACCUCCCUACCCAUCCCCACCUCCCUACCCAUCCCCACCUCCCUACCCAUCCCCACCUCCCUACCCAUCCCCACCUCCCUACCCAUCCCCACCUCCCUACCCAUCCUAUGAUGUCCAAAGAAACCAGACAGAGCAAAUUGGCCGAGGCCAAGGAACAGUUGACAGACCAUCAUCCCCAGACCAACCCUAGUGUUGGUACAGCAGCAAGCGACACCAAAAAGAAGAAAAUAAAUAAUGGCACUAGCCCUGAGACAACCACUUCUGGUGGUUGCCACUCGCCUGAGGAUGAACAGAAGGCAAGCCACCAACAUCAGGAAGCCCUAAGGAGGGAGCUAGAGGCCCAGGUUCAUACCAUACGAAUCCUUACAUGUCAGAAAACUGAGCUUCAGAUGGCACUCUACUACAGCCAGCAUGCUGUCAAGCAGUUGGAAGGAGAGGCCAGGGAUCUGAUCAGCCGCCUGCAUGAUUCAUGGAAGUUUGCAGGAGAGUUAGAGCAGGCUCUCUCUGCUGUCACUACACAGAAGAAGAAGGCGGAUAGGUACAUUGAGGAGUUAACAAAGGAGAGGGACGCCCUGAGUCUGGAACUGUACAGGAACACCAUAACUGAUGAGGAGCUGAAGGAGAAAAAUGCCAAACUACAAGAAAAACUUCAACUUGUAGAAUCUGAAAAGUCUGAGAUCCAGCUCAACGUAAAGGAGCUAAAAAGGAAACUGGAGAGGGCCAAGCUCCUGCUGCCACAGCAGCAGCUGCAGGCGGAGGCUGACCACCUGGGUAAGGAGCUGCAGAGUGUGUCAGCAAAGCUCCAAGCCCAGGUGGAAGAGAACGAGUUGUGGAACCGCCUGAACCAGCAACAGGAGGAGAAGAUGUGGAGGCAGGAGGAGAAGAUACAGGAGUGGGAGGAGAAGAUACAGGAGCAGGAGGAGAAGAUACGGGAGCAGGAGGAGAAGAUACGGGAGCAGGAGGAGAAGAUGCGGAGGCAGGAGGAGAUGAUGUGGGAGAAGGAGGAGAAGAUGCGGAGGCAGGAGGAGAUGAUGUGGGAGAAGGAGGAGAAGAUACGGGAGCUGGAAGAGAAGAUGCACGAGCAGGAGAAGAUACGGGAGCAGGAAGAGAAGAGGCAGGAGGAGGAGAAGAUACGCGAGCAGGAGAAGAGGCAGGAGCAGGAGGCGAAGAUGUGGAGGCAGGAGGAGAAGAUACGGGAGCAGGAAGAGAAGAUACGGGAGCAGGAGAAAAAGAUGUGGAGGCAGGAGGAGAAGAUUCACGAGCAGGAGAAGAUACGGGAGGAGGAGAAGAGGCAGGAGCAGGAGGAGAUGUGGAGGCAGGAGGAGAAGAUAAGGGAGCAGGAGGAGAUAUGGAGGCAAAAGGAGAAGAUGCACGAGCAGGAGGAGAAGAUACGGAAGCAGGAGGAGAAGGUGUGGAGGCAGGAGGAGAAGAUGCACGACCAGGAGGAGAAGAUACGGGAGCAGGAGGAGAAGGUGUGGAGGCAGGAGGAGAAGAUACGGGAGCAGGAGAAGAAACGGGAGCAGGAGGAGAAGAUGUGGAGGCAGGAGGAGAAGAUACGGGAGCAGGAGGAGAAGAUACGGGAGCAGGAGGAGAUGUGGAGGGAGGAAGAGAAGAUGCAUGAGCAGGAGAAGAUAUGGGAGGAGGAGAAGAGGCAGGAGCAGGAGGAUAAGAUGUGGAGGCAGGAGGAGAAGAUACGGGAGCAGGAGGAGAAGGUGUGGAGGCAGGAGGAGAAGAUACGGGAGCAGGAGGAAAAGAGGCAGGAGCAGGAGGAGAAGAUGUGGAAGCAGGAGGAGAAGAUAAGGGAGCAGGAGGAGAAGAUACGGGAGCAGGAGGAGAAGAUACGGGAGCAGGAGGAGAAGAUACGAGAGCAGGAGGAGAUGAUGCAGGAACAGGAAGAGAAGAUGGGGGAGCAGGAAGAGAAGAUGCAAGAACAGGAGAAGAUGCGGAGGCAGGAGGAGAAGAUAAGGGAGCAGGAGGAGAAGAUACGGGAGCAGAAGGAGAAGAUACGAGAGCAGGAGGAGAAGAUAUGGGAGCAGGAGGAGAAGAUACGAGAGCAGGAGGAGAUGAUGCAGGAACAGGAAGAGAAGAUGGGGGAGCAGGAGGAGAAGAUUUGGGAGCAGGAAGAGAAGAUGCAAGAACAGGAGGAGAAGAUGCGGAGGCAGGAGGAGAAGAUAAGGGAGCAGGAGAAGAAGAUACGGGAGCAGGAGGAGAAGAUACGAGAGCAGGAGGAGAUGAUGCAGGAACAGGAAGAGAAGAUGGGGGAGCAGGAAGAGAAGAUGCAAGAACAGGAGGAGAAGAUGCGGAGGCAGGAGGAGAAGAUAAGGGAGCAGGAGAAGAAGAUACGGGAGCAGGAGGAGAAGAUACGAGAGCAGGAGGAGAUGAUGCAGGAACAGGAAGAGAAGAUGUGGGAGCAGGAGGAGAAGAUGUGUGAGCAGGAAGAGAAGAUGCAAGAACAGGAGGAGAAGAUGCGGAGGCAGGAGGAGAAGAUGUGGGAGCAGGAAGUGAGGCUGCGGCAGCAGGAGGAGAAGAUGCAGGAACACUAGGAGCACCUGGAAGCUGCCAUCUAAUGAGCACAUGACAAGAAGGCAAAGACAAUAAACAUGUAAAAGCCGGCAGCAAGGCCUGGAGAAGAGUAAGCCGCCAUGUGACUGUUUAGAAUAUAGUCUGAGCACAAACCUGAAAAAAAAAUUUUAUUUAUUUUAAAUUGUGGCAAAAUACUGGCCAGGCAUGGUAGCUCACGCCUGUAAUCCUAGCAAUUUGGGAGGCCGAGGUAAAUGGAUGACCUGAGGUCAAGAGUUCAAGACCAGCCUGGCCAAUACAAAAAUUAGCCGGGCAUGGUGGCGCAUGCCUGUAAUCCCAGCUACUUGGGAGGCUGAGGCAGGAGAAUCGCUUGAACCUGGGAGGCAGAGGUUGCAGUGAGCUGAGAUCGUGCCACUGCACUCAAGCCUGGGUGACAGAGCGAAACUCCGUCUCAAAAAAAAAAGUUUCUUCCUUACAUGUAUGUUUCUAUUAGUUUUCUUCUUGGUCUUUCUCAUUUAGUCUUGUGUUGUCUUUUGACAUUCAUAGUAAACUUUUAUCUGCCUCCAGAGAGUAUUGACUUUGAGUUUAUGGCACACAAUUGGAGUAAGGGCAGAUCGCCUUCAUCUACUUUGGGACUAAGCUGGUUCAAAGCAGGUUUUAGGUUUUCUGAUGGCUGGUCUAUGUUUUAUUCAUCUGGACUCCCAGGGGUGGCCCUUCCAGGGUCCCCACCAAGGUCCCAUCUCCUUCCUGGGACCCAAAUUCUCAUUAGGUCAUUUCAGCCCUGUGAGAGUGCCAAACAUUCAGCUAGGCUCUCCAGCCUCUUAACUACCACUUCAUACUCAGUUUCUUAGCCUCUUAGCCCUCUACUGUUGACCAAUCACCAAAUGUGGGAAAGCACUACAGACUGUCAGGAUCACCUCCUAGGCCUGGUCACUCAAGUCCUGACUGAGGUCUCCAAUUACCUUCCAACAAUUGUUUUUGAUUGGGGGCGGGGCACAUUUUUAUCCAGUUUUUCUAACUGCUCUUGUGGGGAGGCGAAUCUGUAACAAGCUCCUCUGCCUUUAUUGAAAGUUGAAAACCUUCAUCUGUCCUUUUUUUGUUGUUGUUGAGAUGGAGUCUUGCGCUGUUGCCCAGGCUCUAGUGCAAUGGCACGAUCUCUGCUCACUGUAACCUCUGCCUCCUGGGUUCAAGCAAUUCUCCUGCCUCAGCUUCCCGAGUAGCGUGUGCCACCAUGCCUGGCUAAUUUUUUUUUAUACCUUUAAUAGAGGCAGGAUUUCACCAUGUUUUCCAGGCUGGUCUCGAGCUCCUGACUCAGGUGAUCUACCUGCCUCAGCCUCCCAAAGUGCUGGGAUUACAAGUAUGAGCCACUGCAUCCGGCCCAUCUGUCUUUUAAAACAUGUUUUUAAUUGGAGGUAUAAUUUCUAUUAGUGAAAUGCACAGGUCUGGUUUACAUUUUGAUGAGUUUUAACUCAUUUAACAUUACUAUGGAACCCACCUCCUUUGAAGAUACAGAGUAUUUCUAUCAUCCAGAAAGUUCUCCUGUGCUUUCAUGCUGUCCCGCACUCCCCCAGCCAGCUGAUGAACAUGCUGAGGACAUUGGUACUGGAUUCUGGCCGCCCCAAAAGAGCCACUUUGACCAGGCUUACCCAGCACUAAAUCCCUGCCUGCUCUCUCAAAAUUUCCAUCUUUAAACUGGUUGUACCUAUAACCCUCCCUCAUCAAGUCAAUAGAUAAACAAACCCUGAAAAAUAAACAACUCUUCCUGGCC